AGGCCGCCAGCCUCGGAGUGGGCGCGGGACAGUGCGCGGCGCCCCGCAGCCAGGCCCCCGCCCCCGCCGCAUCCACCUCCUCCGCCGCCUGCGACCCAACGGGCGCCCCCCGCCGCGGCAGCUGCCGCCGGGCCCCCGCGGCCACCAUGAAGAAGGAGGUGUGCUCCGUGGCCUUCCUCAAGGCCGUGUUCGCAGAGUUCUUGGCCACCCUCAUCUUCGUCUUCUUUGGCCUGGGCUCGGCCCUCAAGUGGCCGUCGGCGCUGCCUACCAUCCUGCAGAUCGCGCUGGCGUUUGGCCUGGCCAUAGGCACGCUGGCCCAGGCCCUGGGACCCGUGAGCGGCGGCCACAUCAACCCCGCCAUCACCCUGGCCCUCUUGGUGGGCAACCAGAUCUCGCUGCUCCGGGCUUUCUUCUACGUGGCGGCCCAGCUGGUGGGCGCCAUUGCCGGGGCUGGCAUCCUCUACGGUGUGGCACCGCUCAAUGCCCGGGGCAAUCUGGCCGUCAACGCGCUCAACAACAACACAACGCAGGGCCAGGCCAUGGUGGUGGAGCUGAUUCUGACCUUCCAGCUGGCACUCUGCAUCUUCGCCUCCACUGACUCCCGCCGCACCAGCCCUGUGGGCUCCCCAGCCCUGUCCAUUGGCCUGUCUGUCACCCUGGGCCACCUUGUCGGAAUCUACUUCACUGGCUGCUCCAUGAACCCAGCCCGCUCUUUUGGCCCUGCGGUGGUCAUGAAUCGGUUCAGCCCCGCUCACUGGGGUCUGCUUCUAUCCCUGCGUGGAGGGGACACGCGCUCUGUUCAUCCGUCUCUCUGAGGACCCACGUGUCCCCUCUGAAGGUUUUCUGGGUAGGGCCCAUCGUGGGGGCGGUCCUGGCUGCCAUCCUUUACUUCUACCUGCUCUUCCCCAACUCCCUGAGCCUGAGUGAGCGUGUGGCCAUCAUCAAAGGCACGUAUGAGCCUGACGAGGACUGGGAGGAGCAGCGGGAAGAGCGGAAGAAGACCAUGGAGCUGACCACCCGCUGACCAGUGUCAGGCAGGGGCCAGCCCCUCAGCCCCUGAGCCAAGGGGGAAAAGAAGAAAAAGUACCUAACACAAGCUUCCUUUUUGCACAACCGGUCCUCUUGGCUGAGGAGGAGGAGCUGGUCACCCUGGCUGCACAGUUAGAGAGGGGAGAAGGAACCCAUGAUGGGACUCCUGGGGUAGGGGCCAGGGGCUGGGGUCUGCUGGGGACAGGUCUCUCUGGGACAGACCUCAGAGAUUGUGAAUGCAGUGCCAAGCUCACAGGCUGCAAGGGCCAGGCCAGAAAAGGGCGGGCCUGCAGCCUGCACCCCCCACCUUCCCCAACCCUUCCUCAAGAGCUGAAGGGAUCCCAGCCCCUAGGUGGGCAGAGGCAGACCCUCCCCAGAGCUCCUUAGGAAGAAGACAGACUGGUUCAUUGAAUGCCGCCUUAUUUAUUUCUGGUGAGGAUGCAUGCGUGGGGCUGCUGGUGUUUAGAGUGGGGGCUACCCAAUAAAUCACUGAUACUCAC